GCUAGAGCAGUUGUGUGAGCUGAUUAAAUAGCGUAUUUGAGGUUUUCGCUUCUGUGUCUGGUGCUGCUGUCUAAAGUCCACGGAUUUAAGAAGGAAAGCUGGAUGUUAGGAGGGGACGCAGGGGAAGCUAGAACCUGGGAGGAGGGACUGGAGCUCUGGAGGAUGGUCGAAUCUCAAGCCAGGAGGAGGUGAGCAGGAGCUGGAGAAGCUGUGAGCACACUGCCGUCACCCACCCCCUGCAGGGCAGCAGAUGAGACUCGGAGUGCCGAGCUUGUGGUGGCGUCUGGCACUUGACACAGACAUACUGAGGGCAGAGAGCAAGCUACUGCUGCACUUCCGCCUUCAAAAUCUCACGCAAUUGCCUCUUGUGGGGAACACUAACCCGGAGCGGUGCAAGGAAAAGUCUUUUCAGCUUCGCGAAGUUGACACAAUAUAAACCCACUGUGCAUCGAUUAACCCUCGGCCAGGAAACAUCUUUGUGGUGAGCUUAGCGGUGGCAGACCUGGUGGUGGCCAUUUAUCCGUACCCGUUGGUGCUGAUGUCGAUAUUUAACAACGGGUGGAACCUGGGCUAUCUGCACUGCCAAGUCAGUGGGUUCCUGAUGGGCCUGAGCGUCAUCGGCUCCAUAUUCAACAUCACCGGCAUCGCCAUCAACCGCUACUGCUACAUCUGCCACAGUCUCAAGUACGACAAACUGUACAGCAGCAAGAACUCCCUCUGCUACGUGCUCCUCAUAUGGCUCCUGACGCUGGCGGCCGUCCUGCCCAACCUCCGUGCAGGGACUCUCCAGUACGACCCGAGGAUCUACUCGUGCACCUUCGCCCAGUCCGUCAGCUCCGCCUACACCAUCGCCGUGGUGGUUUUCCACUUCCUCGUCCCCAUGAUCAUAGUCAUCUUCUGUUACCUGAGAAUAUGGAUCCUGGUUCUCCAGGUCAGACAGAGGGUGAAACCUGACCGCAAACCCAAACUGAAACCACAGGACUUCAGGAAUUUUGUCACCAUGUUUGUGGUUUUUGUCCUUUUUGCCAUUUGCUGGGCUCCUCUGAACUUCAUUGGCCUGGCCGUGGCCUCUGACCCCGCCAGCAUGGUGCCUAGGAUCCCAGAGUGGCUGUUUGUGGCCAGUUACUACAUGGCGUAUUUCAACAGCUGCCUCAAUGCCAUUAUAUACGGGCUACUGAACCAAAAUUUCAGGAAGGAAUACAGGAGAAUUAUAGUCUCGCUCUGUACAGCCAGGGUGUUCUUUGUGGACAGCUCUAACGACGUGGCCGAUAGGGUUAAAUGGAAACCGUCUCCACUGAUGACCAACAAUAAUGUAGUAAAGGUGGACUCCGUUUAAAAAAGCACCACGUUCCGGGUGAGAUGGACACGCU